UUUGGCACCUGUGCGCUGGACUCGAGCGCUCCGAUUGGAGUUAGGGCCUGCUUGUCUGCGUGCUGCGAAGUCCGCGGCUGCCCCCGGGGCCCUAGUCGUUGGGUUCCAGGGUCCUUCACGUUCCAUUCCCAGGCUGGUCUGAGCUCCGGGGCCGUGGUCCCGCUGCCUCCUCCGGUCGUCGUGCGGAAGCUGCGACGCAGGUACAGCUGGAGCGCGGCGGGGCGGCCCCCAGGGUCACCGGGCUCGGGGCUUGGCGCGCGACGGAACGCAGAUCGGGGGCGUGGCCCGCGAUCACCGCUGGGGAAGGCGGGGAGGGGACCUUUGGGGGACCAAGGGCAGCGUUCGAAUCCUAGCCCAGCCCCCUUCCCCUCUCGGUCUCUUGGUUUAUCCUGCGAACGGGGCGUCACCCGCCCACCUAGGGCUGCUGCGCGGCCUGCUCCGCCCGGGCCCAGGGCAGGCAGGUUUGGCGGAGGAGGGAAGGCCAAACGGCCUCCAGGGCCCCGCUGCGCAAACUUGGGUUAUUUUCAGCCACCCGUGCCCUUUCCUGCUUCUCGGAGCUGGAAGGCUGUGGACUGAGGCCUGCGCGACCCCGCCAGAGAUGGGGCUGAGUCCCAAUUUAGACAGGUUGGGAGUAUUUAAAGCGCUUUACAGUUUGCAAAGUAGAUUCCUGGUCUCUCUGGGGGCGGGUGGCAGUAUUGAUCCCCGAGUCACCGAUGAGGAGAUUGAAACCGGCCCUGGGGCCGUGGCGGGUCACCCGGUUGGCCUGGGAUCGCCCCAGAGACCGUCUUAUUUUUAGUCUGGGGCGAAUGGGCGGGUGUACGGGGCUGAGUCACACAGCGCUUCAGGCUUCAGCUACUCCAGGCAUCUGGUCACCUGGCAACUGGGCCCCUGGCACCCACACUCUGGCAGGGCAGGUAGAAGUCCUUGGUGCCCGGGCAGGCUGUGACCUCAUGGUCAUCUGCUCAGGCCUCCCCGGGAGAGUUCUGCUUGGUGUCUAACUGAUGUCCUAAGGUCCCAGCCCUUCUCAGCUCCCAGGGCCUGAGGGCAGUGUCCCCCUCGCAGAACGUGAGGAAUGUGGACUGGGCCCUAGGAGAUCUUUGCCUCCACUUCCCAAGUGCUGGCCCCCACCCAGCCACACACUUCAAGGCUGCCCACAUCUGCCCCUCACUGCUGCCUAUGCCAUCUUACAGGCAGACCAUGGCAGAGUUCUCCCAGAAACGGGGGAAGCGGCGUAGCGACGAAGGGCUGGGCAGCAUGGUGGACUUCCUCCUGGCCAAUGCCCGCCUGGUGCUGGGCGUGGGCGGGGCUGCUGUGCUGGGCAUUGCCACCCUGGCCGUGAAGCGGUUCAUUGACAGGGCCACUAGCCCGCGGGAUGAGGAUGACACCAAGGCAGACAGCUGGAAGGAACUGAGCCUGCUCAAGGCCACACCACACCUGCAGCCCCGGCCUCCACCUGCUGCCCUUAGCCAGCCAGUGUUGCCCUUGGCCCCCUCGUCGUCUGCCCCAGAAGGGCCUGCAGAAACUGAUCCUGAGGUGACACCACAGCUCAGCUCCCCAGCACCGCUGUGUCUGACACUGCAGGAGAGGCUGCUGGCCUUCGAGCGGGACCGUGUGACCAUCCCAGCAGCCCAGGUGGCUUUGGCCAAACAGCUGGCUGGCGACAUCGCCCUGGAGCUGCAGGCCUACUUUCGGAGCAAGUUCCCGGAACUGCCCUUUGGGGCAUUCGUGCCUGGGGGGCCGCUCUACGACGGGCUGCAGGCGGGGGCUGCGGACCAUGUGCGUCUCCUGGUGCCACUGGUGCUGGAGCCGGGCCUGUGGAGCCUGGUGCCGGGCGUGGACACUGUGGCGAGGGACCCUCGCUGCUGGGCCGUGCGCAGGACGCAGCUUGAGUUCUGCCCCCGUGGGAGCAGCCCCUGGGACCGCUUCCUGGUCGGGGGCUACCUCUCCUCCCGCGUCCUGCUGGAGCUACUCCGCAAGGCGCUGGCUGCUUCUGUCAACUGGCCGGCCAUUGGCAGCCUUCUCGGGUGCCUGAUCCGGCCCAGCAUGGCCUCGGAGGAGCUGCUGCUCGAGGUGCAGCACGAACGCCUGGAGCUCACUGUGGCUGUGCUUGUGGCAGUCCCUGGGGUCGAUGCUGACGACCGCCUCCUCUUGGCCUGGCCCCUGGAGGGGCUGGCGGGGAACCUCUGGCUGCAGGACCUGUAUCCAGUGGAGGCUGCUAGGCUGCGAGCCCUGGACGACCAUGACGCUGGGACUCGCCGGCGGCUGCUGCUGCUGCUGUGUGCUGUCUGCCGUGGUUGCUCGGCUCUGGGGCAGCUAGGCCGGGGUCACCUGACCCAGGUGGUCCUGCGUCUGGGGGAGGACAACGUGGAUUGGACGGAGGAGGCCUUGGGUGAGCGCUUCCUGCAAGCCCUGGAGCUGCUCAUCGGCAGCCUGGAGCAGGCCAGCCUGCCCUGCCACUUCAACCCCAGCGUGAACCUCUUCAGCAGCUUGCGUGAGGAGGAGAUUGACGACAUUGGCUAUGCGCUAUACAGUGGCCUACAGGAGCCCGAGGGGCUGCUCUAGGUGGGUGGAAACGGGUGGUUGCCAUGUUUUCUAAUGCUGGGGAGCUGCACCCACCUCCCUUCCAGGGAUUUGAAUAGUGGUUUUUCUCUAGCUUUUUGCCAGAACAAAGGAGGGUACAUUACUUAAACCCAGGGCAUCAGGAUGUGCUUGGGCUAUGGUGGCCAUAAACCCUGAGCCCAGAGAGCUUGGGUCACUGUCACCUGAGUGCAGCUGGGCUGCCUCAGGCAGCUUGGAGUGCCAGCCAUUCCUGCAAGCACCGUUUCAGCUCUUGGGGCCAACCCCAGGACCUUUGGCUCUGUCCAUCACCAGCAACCAAUCCACCAACAGAAUGUGGUUUCUGCCAUCCUGGGCAGAAGCUGAAGGCCAGCUUCACAUUUCUGCUGAGAGAAGGUGACUUAACGCCUUUUCCGGCCCUAGCUCCAGGCGUUUUGAGGCGUCUGGUGCCUGAUGGUAGGUAUGGUGUGUUUGUUCUGUCCCCCAGGGGCUGGAGUCACCUGGUGCCCCUGAAGGACAGAUUUUUGGCUGUUAAAGGAUGGCAUUUUCCUGCUGUCUUCUGUGCGUUUAGUUUUCUUGCUGAGCGGGAGCUCAGUAUGACUUGCCACCCACCUGAUACCUCAGGGCAAGGCCCUUUUUCCCUCCAGCCAGGUGAGUGUUUUCUUCAGGCAGCUGAGGGUCCUGGGGGAGCUGAGGCUCUGUGCUGCACCCCCAGCCCACAGCUGGGGCAUCUCACUGGAGCUGUUCCAGGCCCCACUGGAGAGCAGAGGACCUGAUCCCCCACUAGAGAGGUCCGGUGUGCACAGCCGGCCUCCCAGUGUGCCAAAAUGAACUGCUCUCAGCUGAUGGCUGUAUUCUGACUUUGAAGCCUGUUAAGAGGUAGCAAGGGGGCUAGAGGAGGGAGAUUCCACCUCCCCUCCCAAGUGACCCUCCUCCUGCCUCUGGUAUCCUUCCUUUUGAAACGAAGCUCAGCUUCGAAGAUGUGAACAAGAAUAAAAGGAAAAAAUUCUAAUGUAUAUAUAACUCAGGCUGGAUAAGGGAGUCUUGGUGCUUUCAUACGCAGCUGUUGAGGGUUUUCUGUAAGUCCUGUGGCUUGUCCUGGCACUUUGGCAAGAGUGCUUGAGGUCAAUUGGAGGUGGUAGAGUUUACUUUAAAAAGUAGCAUCUUGGCCGGGUGUGGUGGCUCGCAUCUGUAAUCCCAGCACAUCGGGAGGCCGAGGCGGGCGGAUCACGAGGUCAAGAGAUCGAGACCAUCCUGACCAACAUGAUGAAACCCCAACUCUACUAAAAAGACAAAAAUUAGCUGGGCGUGGUGGCACGCACCUAUAGUCCCAGCUACUCGGGAGGCCGAGGCAGGAGAAUUGCUUGAACCCGGGAGGUAGAGGUUGCAAUGAGCUGAAAUUGCACCACUGCACUCCAGACUGGCGACAGAGCAAGACUCUGUCUCAAAAAAAUAAAUAAAUAAGCAUCUUGGCCCCGCGCUGUGGCUCACGCCUAUAAUCCCAGCACUUUGGGAAGCCGAGGCCGGUAGAUCACCUGAGGUUGGGAAUUCAAGACCAGGCUGACCAACGUGGAGAAACUCCAUCUCUGGUAAAAAUUCAAAAAAAUUAGCUGGGCAUGGUGGCACAUGCCUGUAAUCCCAGCUACUUGGGAGGCUGAGGCAGGAGAAUUGCUUGAACCCGGGAGGCGGAGGUUGUGGUGAGCUGAGAUCGUGCCAGUGCACUCCAGCCUAGGCAACAAGAGUGAAACUCUGUCUCAAAAUAAAAUAAAAUAAAAUAAUAAUAGUAAUAAUAAA